AGGGUUAAACGACUGGAGGAGGGACAGGUGGGGCGGGGGUCUGCAGACCAGGUUGGCAACACUGGUGAGUUGCUCUUCUUUCGCCCUCCUUCCCUUCUUCUAUCCAAAGGGUGCUGAGCCCGGGAGGAGGUGGGAGGUGCCCCGCGGAGCCGGGAGUGAGCGUUCCCGAGGCAGCAGGCACCUUCGAGAGGGACUGGCAUUUGGGCCCAGGAGCCAGGAAAAAGUCCUGAGCGUGCCGGCCUCGAGGAAGGCACGUUCCCUAAGGGCGCACGGUCACUGCAGUCUUUCACCGUCCGUCUGUUUUUAGAACAGAGUUCUGGCCUGAGCUUAUAAAUCUCGGGCUUUGCCCCCAAACCCCAGGCCUUUUGCGGACGGAACAGGUGAGCACUGCGCACUGCUCGCGCCCCGGUUCUUGCGUCCCCUGCUCUCCCUGCGCUCUGAGCGGCCUGGCCCCCGCGGGCUCAUCAUGUUCCCUUGGGGGCUGAGCUGCCUGUCAGUGCUGGGGGCGGCGGGCACUGCUCUCCUGUGCGCGGGCCUGCUGCUCAGCCUGGCCCAGCACCUCUGGACCCUCCGCUGGAUGCUGAGCCGGGACCGGGCCUCCACCCUGCCUCUGCCCAAGGGCUCCAUGGGGUGGCCCUUCUUCGGCGAAACGCUGCACUGGUUAGUUCAGGGCUCGCGCUUCCACAGUUCUCGCCGAGAGCGCUAUGGGACAGUGUUCAAGACGCACCUGCUGGGCAGGCCAGUGAUCCGCGUGAGCGGCGCGGAGAACGUGCGCACCAUCCUGCUGGGCGAGCACCGCCUGGUGCGCAGCCAGUGGCCGCAGAGUGCGCACAUCCUGCUGGGCUCGCACACACUGCUAGGUGCGGUCGGCGAGCCGCACCGGCGGCGGCGCAAGGUCCUGGCGCGCGUGUUCAGCCGCGCCGCGCUGGAGCGCUACGUGCCGCGCCUGCAGGGGGCGCUGCGGCAUGAGGUGCGCUCCUGGUGCGCGGCGGGCGGGCCGGUCUCAGUCUACGACGCCUCCAAAGCGCUCACCUUCCGCAUGGCCGCGCGCAUCCUGCUGGGGUUGCGGCUGGACGAGGCGCAGUGCGCCACGCUGGCCCGGACCUUCGAGCAGCUCGUGGAGAACCUCUUCUCACUGCCUCUGGACGUUCCCUUCAGUGGCCUACGCAAGGGCAUCCGGGCAAGGGACCAGCUGCAUCGGCACCUGGAGGGGGCCAUUUCUGAGAAGCUUCACGAGGACAAGGCUGCAGAGCCGGGUGAUGCCCUCGACCUAAUCAUUCACAGUGCAAGGGAGCUGGGCCAUGAGCCCUCCAUGCAGGAGCUGAAGGAGUCGGCUGUGGAGCUCCUCUUCGCCGCCUUCUUCACCACGGCCAGUGCCAGCACCUCGCUCGUCCUGCUGCUACUGCAGCAUCCGGCGGCCAUCGCCAAGAUUCGGGAGGAGCUGGUGGCGCAGGGGCUGGGGCGCGCGUGCGGCUGCGCGCCCGGGGCCGCUGGGGGCAGCGAGGGGCCCCCGCCCGACUGCGGCUGCGAGCCCGACCUCAGCCUCGCGGCGCUGGGCCGUCUGCGCUACGUCGACUGCGUGGUCAAGGAGGUGCUGCGCCUCCUGCCGCCAGUGUCCGGGGGCUACCGCACCGCCCUGCGCACCUUCGAGCUCGACGGCUACCAGAUCCCCAAGGGCUGGAGCGUGAUGUAUAGCAUCCGGGACACGCACGAGACGGCUGCGGUGUACCGCAGCCCUCCCGAAGGCUUCGAUCCAGAGCGCUUCGGCGCAGCGCGCGAAGAUUCCCGGGGCGCCUCCAGCCGCUUCCAUUACAUCCCGUUCGGCGGCGGUGCGCGCAGCUGCCUCGGCCAGGAGCUGGCGCAAGCCGUGCUCCAGCUGCUAGCUGUGGAGCUAGUGCGCACCGCGCGCUGGGAACUGGCCACACCCGCCUUCCCCGCCAUGCAGACGGUGCCCAUCGUGCACCCAGUGGACGGGCUGCGGCUCUUUUUCCACCCCCUCACGCCUUCGGUUGCGGGGAAUGGGCUAUGCCUCUGACAUGCUUGCGCUCUAGGACACGGCUUGGCCGGUGGCUAUGGCGCGCACGCAGCGCCACCCAUCUGCCGCUCCCCAUUGUAGCGUCGCGCGCCCACUCUUUCACUCGUUCAACAAUCUUUCAACAAAUGUUCGCCAAACGCGGAUGUGUGCCGGACUCGAGGAAGGAGGAGGGCGAGCCACCGCUGCCGCGCCAGAGAAGCAUCUAAGCCCAUGGGAAGAUGCCUUCUGCGCUCCGCGCCCAGAGGAAGGAAAAUGUCGUGGGCCAAGCAGGAAUGGAGGGAAUAGAUAGAUCCCCACGAGGUGCUGCUUGGCUUCCCCUUCCCGAGCCAAUCCAGGGAGGGUGCAUGGAUGGGGGAAGGCGAGGUAGGGGUGGCAGGGGAGUGGGAAUAUUGCAACUCGGGGACAUUGCAGAGACCCGACGCACGCGGUGGGACCUGCAACCCUUGUAAGGAAGCGGGCACGCCGUGGGCGCAACCCUGGCCUGGCUUUGGGCCAUAGAAAAAACACGCAGAGGAUGCCUGACGGAAGGCCCUCUGGCAGCUGGCGUCUGGCUUCGUGCGCCUUGGCCACUCUGCCGGUCUCGGCGGAAACUAGCAACUGUGGGCACUUCCAGGCUCGAAAGGGCUCAAGGUCACCGGAUUCUGCUGGCCACUUCUUAAAAGGAAAAAUUCCUACCUUAAGAAGGCAUUUACUCUUGUCAUGUAUACAGAGGAGAAUAGGCACACCAACACGUCUCCAACGCUGGAUUAUUUUCAUGGGAGGUUGAGACAUAAUUAGAGAGGUUUGAGAUAUUUGUACCAAAAAUAGGAAGGCCAAGAAAUAAAGUGUCUUGGGAGCGGUUGA